GCUUUACAAUAGAAGCUCGGUUGGAGAGGCCUGCGGAGAAAAGCUGGGAACGGCCGCUUCCGGCAUGUUCAUCUCUGGACGAAGAACGGCCGACAAGUGGAGGGCGGAGGAGAGACUCCAAUGCCCAGCGGGCAGUGCGCGGGCGGCGCUUGCGCGAUGCGCGGACGGGGGGGCGGUCGGGCCAUUUAAAUGUGUGUUUGUGGGUGAAAUGGCUGCGCAGGUCGGAGCGGUGCGCGUAGUACGGGCGGUGGCGGCGCAGGAGGAGCCGGACAAAGAGGGGAAGGAGAAACCUCAUGCUGGGGUCUCCCCGCGGGGAGUUAAACGGCAGCGCCGAUCUAGCAGUGGGGGGUCUCAGGAGAAGCGGGGGCGGCCGAGCCAGGAGCCCCCUCUCGCUCCCCCUCACCGGCGGCGUCGCAGCCGCCAACAUCCUGGGCCGCUGCCGCCAACGAAUGCAGCCCCAACUGUCCCAGGCCCUGUUGAGCCUCUUCUCCUGCCGCCUCCGCCGCCACCUUCGCUGGCACCCGCCGGGCCCGCUGUCGCUGCCCCUCUCCCGGCCCCAAGCACCUCGGCCCUCUUCACCUUCUCGCCUCUGACGGUGAGCGCGGCCGGGCCCAAGCAUAAGGGCCACAAGGAGCGGCACAAGCACCAUCACCACCGCGGCCCCGAUGGUGAUCCCAGCUCCUGCGGAACCGAUCUCAAGCACAAGGACAAGCAGGAAAACGGCGAGAGGACUGGAGGGGUGCCUCUGAUCAAAGCCCCCAAGAGAGAAACACCAGAUGAAAAUGGUAAAACCCAGAGAGCCGAUGAUUUUGUCUUGAAGAAAAUAAAGAAGAAAAAGAAAAAGAAACACCGAGAAGACAUGCGAGGAAGACGCCUUAAAAUGUACAAUAAGGAAGUACAAACCGUCUGUGCUGGCCUGACCCGCAUCAGUAAAGAAAUUCUCACCCAAGGACAAAUAAAUAGCACUUCAGGACUUAAUAAGGAGUCCUUCAGGUAUCUGAAAGAUGAACAGCUGUGCCGAUUAAAUUUGGGUAUGCAAGAAUAUCGGGUACCCCAGGGAGUACAAACACCUUUUAUGACUCACCAGGAACAUUCUAUUCGUAGAAAUUUCUUAAAAACAGGUACUAAAUUUAGCAACUUUAUUCAUGAGGAACACCAGUCCAAUGGUGGUGCUCUUGUCCUUCAUGCUUACAUGGAUGAACUCUCAUUUUUGUCUCCAAUGGAGAUGGAGAGAUUUUCUGAGGAGUUUCUUGCUUUGACAUUCAGUGAAAAUGAGAAAAAUGCUGCUUACUAUGCUUUAGCAAUAGUGCAUGGAGCGGCUGCUUAUCUCCCAGACUUCUUGGACUACUUUGCUUUUAAUUUCCCCAACACUCCAGUGAAAAUGGAAAUUCUGGGCAAGAAAGAUAUUGAAACAACCACCAUUUCAAAUUUUCACACUCAGUAGAGAGAGCAGGAGCAGCCAAUGUGGAGAGGUCGCAAGAUGGGGCUGCCCAAGAUGUUGGAACACCAUGUGCAAUAAAGGGCUUCGUCUUGGAUUUUGGCCUUAUUACCACAACCAGGUACCGAAGUGCUGACUUUUGUAGUAGAUUUUCUUUUUUCAUUUUCAUUUUUUUUUUAAGUUUUGCCCUUUGAAGGUCAAGGAAUCCUAUUUUUAUAAAUAUUGCAGAUGAGACUGAAAACAUUUCUCCUAAUAUAGUCCAUAAUCCCCAUAAGUUCCCUAUUUAACAAGGAAAGAUAUUGCUGAGAGCAGAAUCAACAUGCUCUAUCAUUUUUUUAGUUUAGAAAAAUGCAGCAAAUUUUCUCUUUUGAUAGACCAACAAGCAUUUCUGAGAAAUAAGCCAGAAAUUUGGGGGAAAACUGUCCCAGUUUUGUAAGGGUGUCUUUUUAACAUUCAUAUUAGUUAAAGUGGAUCAAAUUUGUAUGUCAACAGACAGUAUCCAGUCUAAAUAGUUAAUAAAAGAAAAUAUCUUGAAAUAUUCCCUGCUGAUUUUUGUCCUCCAAUUAAUUUUUUAAAAUGGAGCUGAAAUUUAAAUGACUGUACCAACAACUUACCUUGAUACUUACUUUGAGAUUUAAAAAAUAACCACUUUUUAAGAACAUUUCAGAUUAUGAUUAAAUUAGAUAUUAAACGCUUCAACCACAUAAGAAUAUUGAGGACUGUUGAAUGAGUCCUGUGCUCUGGUGGUCCUGGAACUUAAUUUUAUUUAUGAAUUUUCAGUCAUUAGAGAAGAGUAUGGUGUGGAUAUGGGAGGUUGGAUUAGCCGACUAAACUUUGAAGUUUGCAACUUUAGCAGAUGUUGGGAUAGAAGUUAACACAGUAGUUCAAAUUGAUUUCGCACUUCAUGGUUUAUAGAAAUGCUUUCACAUUCAUAUCUGAAUAUUUGAAACAACCUAGUGGGUAGGUAGGUAAGCAAUUUUAUCUGUGUUUCCCAUGGAAGAAACUGAGGCUGGGAGAUGUUCAUUGUUUGUUAUCCAAGGUCAUAUAGCUAGUAAGUAGAAGAGUCCAGAUGCAAACCCAGGCCACCUGAACAAUGUUCACAUCAUUUUACCAUGGAGAAGAGAUUAGUGCUUUUAUUUGUCUAACACUCUGGUCAGUGAAAUUAAAGUAUCUCCGUGUGAAACAGCAUGCAAAAGGCUUUGUUUCUAAUAUUUUUAACAAAUCCCUUUAGAUCGUUGGGAAUUAAACAAAUACCUAGGGCAGUGUGGACUUACCUGAAGUCUUUUGACAUUUUAUGAAGUUCUGUUAAACCUAGAAAUAAAGUCAAAUAAAUUUUUUAUUGCUUUAGAGACAUAGUUAUUGGAAGUUAUUUAUAGUUUAAAUAUGUAGCCAUAAUAAUUAUUCGUGACUAUAUUUCAAGAUAGUUUAUUCAGCAAGCACUUACUGAGAACCUACCAUGUACUGGGCACUGUGUUCUUAAAAGGACUAAUUGAUGAGCUCAGUCUAGUGGGGGAGAUGAGUAAACCAGCAAUUAUAAUACAGAGUACUACUUGAGUAGAGGUACGCAUAGGGAAAACCCUGUAAUAGAGGGAGCACUGUCUGUGUUACCUAAUGCAGACUUGAGGUAAUUCGAAAAGGCAUGUUAAGCCAUGUGAUGCUUGAGUACAAUCUUGAAAGCAUGUUAAUACUUAACUUGGUAAGAACAUUUUAAGCGAAUAACAGCCUAUGCAAAUACACAGAGGCAUUUGAGAAUGCGGCACUUAGAGGGAGCUACAAAUAGAUUGACAUGGCAAGAGUAUGCACUGACUGUUAAGGGAUGGAAGGAGUUGAGACCAGAGAGAGAGAGACAUGAUUAGGAUUGUGAAGAGCCUUAGAUGACAUGCUUUUAAAAAGUUAGUACUUUUUCCUAAAGAUAAUUGGGAGUCAUUGGUGAAUUUUAAUAGGGAAAUGCUUGCUAUCCAUUUAUGUUUGCAAAGAUUACAUAAUAGUGUGGAGGAUGGAAUUGGUGGUGCAGGAUAUGAGAUUGGAAGCAAGAAUACCAGUUAGUUACGAUAGUAACCAUGUCAUAAAUGCUCCACGUCCAAACUGGUACUGACAUUAGAGAGAAAAGAAAGAAAUUUGAGAAAUAAUUAGAAGGUUGAGAUUUAACUAGUCUUGGUGAGAGAGAGAGAUAGUCUUCAGAUGUGGUUUGGACAAAUGGGUGGAUGGCGAUGCUGGUCAAAGCCAAUACAUGGUUGAAAAAGCCGGUUUCUGUGGCUAGAGGGUGUUGAUGAGCUCAGUUUGAGAUAUUUUGAGUUGAAGGUACCUGUGGGAAUUUACGGUUAGAAAUAACUGUUAGGAGGCUGGGCAUGGUGUCUCACAUCUGUAAUCCCAGCAGUUUGGAGGCUGAGGUGAACAGAUUGCUUGAGAUCAGGAAUUUUGAGACCAGCCUGGUCAAAGUGGUGAAACCCCAUGUCUACUAAAAAUUCAAAAAUUAGCUGACAUGGUGGCGGGCGCCUGUAAUCCCAGCUGCUUGGGAUGCUGGCUUGAACCUGGGAGGUGGAGUUUGCACUGAGCCAAGAUCACGUCACUCACUCCAGCCUGGGCGACAGAGCAAGUCUCAAUAAAGAAAAAAAGAAAAAAAAAAAAAGAACUCUUAGGAAUUGAAUGUAUGGAUCCAAGUUUGAGAGAUGUGUCUAGGUUGGAGAUGCAGAAGUUGAACCCAUUAAUGCAGGAGAUGCGGAGAUGCAGAAGAUGGAACCAGCAAUAGCAGUGGAAAAGAGAUGAAACUAAGGGUGGAAUCUUGUGAUGCAUCCACAAGUAAGUAUGAUGAACAUGGGAAAAGACCAAAAAGAAAGGCAGGCAGAAGAAAGACUAGAAGUUUUCUGCAUUUUAAGAAUGAAGUGUUUAUUUUAUCCAUAUGAAGGAUCCAGUAAGUAAGGAUGGGAAAGUGGUAGGUUUAUCAAUUAGGAAUUGAAUUGGAGACAUGAUCAAGAUUAGUGCUUUGCAAACCGUGGACAGGUAAAUACUAUUGUAAAUUAUGCCUUUUCUUUAGAACCUUGCUACUAAAAGUUUGCUCUAUGUAUGAAUUUGGCACCACCAGGGAGCUUGCUAGGAGUGUAGACUGGGCUCUUACCCAGAUUUUCUGAAUCAGAAUCUGCAUUUUUAAAAGGUGAUUCAUAUGCACAUUAAACUUUGAGAAGCUUUAGAACUCAGCUCCUCUAAGCAGGAGAAAGUAAAAUGUAGAUUUUGUGCAAGAAAAAUGAAAACUUCUGUUAUUUUUAUAUUUUUAAAUUAUUGUGGUGGCUAAAGCUAGGAUCCACAUAUAGGGUUUUCUUUUAACAUUCUAGAAAACUCAAAUGUUCUAAUACCAGAGCAGAAAAAUUUAUAUGUCCAUUGAAACAGUAAGCUGAUCCUUGUUUGAUUACUUAACUCUUAGCAGUUGAUACAGGAUAACUUUAUAAAGUUGAGUUUCCUUCCUUCCUCCCUUCCCCUUCCCCUCCCUUCCCUUCCUUUCUUUCUCCUUUCUUUGAUGAGGUCUCGCUCUGUGGCCCAGGCUGAAGUGUGAUCAUGAAGUGUGAUCAUGGCUCACUGAGGCCUUGAACUCCUAGGCUCUAGUAGUCUUUCUACUGUUUCUUACUCCACUGUACCCCAGUACAUAAACUUCAGGAAGUGGUGGAACUCAACUUGUUCUUCGCUUUCAGGUGCUAUUUCCAGUGCCUCAGCCUCUAGAGUAGCUAGGACUACGGGUGUGUACUAUUACAAUUGGCUAAUUUAAAAAUUUUUUUAUAGAGCCAGAGUCUCACUAUGUCGUCUAGGCUAGUCUUGAGCACCUGGUCUCAACGGAUUCUCCUGCUUUGGCCUCCUAGCAUGUUCGGAUUACAGGUGUGAGCACUAGCUUUGCUUAUAGUCUGCAUUUUCUGGUGAUGCUGAUGUUGCUAGUAAAUGGACCACCAAGGCCAUAUAGGUCUCAAAAUCUGUACAUAAAUUGCAAGCGCAAAUAAUAACAAACACUAAAAAUACAGUGAAGUUAAAAGGGAAUUGUUUUCAAUAUCACCUCUGAGAUCUUCUGGCAACUAAGUAAUUGAAGGAUGUACAUGGAGAGGAGUGUGUGUUAUGUGUUUGCUGGGGGUAGGGAAGAUUGGCAAAUCUGCAUGUUUUAAGUAUCUUUUUCAAAAAUUUUCAUAUAUAAUUUUGAGGUUUCACUGAGAAUCAAAGCUUUUUAACUUUAGGUAGUUUUAUUUCUUAUAUUACUUUUAUUACUCUAUAAAAUGAUAAUGUUCUGUAGCAUUGGCGUGUAUAAUUUUAGUGUCUACGGUUCCAGAGAAAAACAAAAAAUGUUAUUCCCUCGUUGUGUGUUGGGACAAGGCCUUAUAUGGGCUUGUUAUAUGCACUCUGAUCUUUGAUUGAUUAACAUUUUAUAAUGAAUUGGUAAUACUAAUAAGAAUAGAACUAGUAGAGUAGUAUAUAGCUUGGGAAAUAGCUCAGAAACCCUUAAGGAACUGUAUGCAUUAUUAGUGUGUUAUAGAAAAGGAGAAAUAAACAUUUUAAGUAGCAGGUUUUAUAAAAUAAAAUGGCAUAAAUAAAAAUGGUAGGCUUGAUUCUUUUUUUUUUCCUCUUAUUUUAAGUACUCACUUUGACCCAGUCACACUGUUUUUUCACUAUAUAUUUUAAAGUAGGAAUGCCUUUCUAUUCACAAGGCACAAGGUUAGGAAGAUCGCUGGCUAAUUUUUUCCUUUCUGUGUUUUAAAAAGUCAGCUUGAAUAGGCUUCUUCCUGAAACGUGAGUUCUGUGGAAUAAUCCACACCCGCUCUCAACCCCCAUACACAGGGUUUUCCACAUAGUGCUUUUUUAGCUUGGUGUUCUCCUGAGUUAUUAACAGAUUUAUAAUUGUCCUUUGUAGAAGCUCUAUGUAUUGGGGACACAGUUGAGCUUACUUAAUUCAGAAAUUCAUACAGGAUAACUGUGAAGUUGAGUUUCUAAUUUAAACACUACAUAUGUAUUGACAGCAGUAUAUAUAUUCAAAGAUAAUUGUUUAACAUUUUAUAGAUAUUAUAAAGAGAAUAAAUUUUAUGCAAAACUAUUAUUUUUUUUAAUAGGCAUAUUUCUCUUUGAUGCCACAUCCUUCUCCCCUCCCCACUUUGCCUUCUGAUUUUACCAAAGACUGUGUUUUUCCUGUUGGCGUUAUGUCUCCUGCUUCCAUGGCAGCUUUAGUUUUUUCUGUUCUUUGGUCUCGUACUUACCUCCCUCCAGUCCUCCCAAUUCUGUUUGUUCCUCCACUGUGCUCCAGUACAUAAACUCCGGAAAGCUGUAGAAUUCAACUUGUUCUUUGUUUUCAGUUGCUAUUUCCAGGCCAGAGUUUCCCAAACUUGCCAGAUCCUAAGAAUAAUUUGGGGUUGCUAGUUCAAAUAUACAUUAGACUCUCAGGUUCCUCUUCUGGAAAUUUUGGUUCAUGAGGUCUGGAGUGAGGCAUGAAAUAAGUACCUUGACCGACUUGAUUCCUAUGAUCAGGCAAGUUUAAGAAACACUGUUUUAAACCAUAUACCAUCUACCAUUACUCUAGUUCCUUUCAUUUGACCUGUAGAUAGCAUCUUUUUAGAAUUUCAGAGCAUCAUAAACUAAGAGAUAAUCUUAUCUGACCUCUACAAAGUGCAAAUUUUAAAAAAUCAUGUUUUGAUUGGCCAUCACUGGGGACUUUGUCUCUUCAUGACAUUUUAUAAUGCUUCCCAUUGGGUUGUCAACAUUGCCUGGGAAGCCUACUUCUUUUCUUUGUUUAGCUUGUUUACCUGUUCUUCAUAAAUACUAUUUAAACUUUAUCUGUAUACAUCUUUUCCUCAUUCUCUCCUGUUACAGUAGAGAAGAUAUUCUAUCUCCUCCUCAAAGGCUAAUUUGUCAGGCUAAUUUGUCUACUUGUGUUAUGAAUACCAUCCCUUAGCCUGCUAAGGUUUUUAAAAAACUGUUGUCAAAUAUACACAAAAUUUACCAUUUUAACCAUUUUAAAGUGUAUAAUUCUGUGGCAUUGGGUAUAUAUAUUGUUCUAUUACCACUACCGUUUCCAGAACUUUUUCCUCAUACCAAACAGAAACUCUAUACCCAUUAGGUUAGGAUCUUUGAUGUCAGUUACCCGCUACUACCCCUCCAACCUUUCCCUUCUCCAUUCCCACUCCCCACGUAACUAAAAGUAUAAAAUAUAUUAAGCGAAUUUCUGCUUCGUGUCUUUCCCCCGCUUUUUUUUUCUCUAAAUAAACUUUUCCUUUCUCCCUAGAAGUAAAUCUUUAUUCUGAAUUUGUGGCUUAUCAUGUCGUUUUAUCUUUUAACAUUUUACUAAUACCAAAUGAACAUAAAAACAAUACUUGUACCUUUGUAUUUUAAAACUACAGUGUAUUGUGUGUAUCAUUCUGCAGGUUAUUUUUGUUCAACAUUGUUUUUGAAGAUUAUUUUGAUACAUCUAACUCUACAUUAAUUUUAACCAUUAUAUUUGGUAUUUUGUUGGGCAGCUGUAUCACUGUUUUUGAACACUUUACUUUUCCUCUGCUCUCAAACAACAGCAAUCAACACAGAAGACUUCUUUGCCCAAAUGUGGGAGAUUUCUCCCCCACAACAAGCAAGCAAUCAGUUCUUCAGCAGACACCAGCUGGGUGUCAUCCAAUUCAAUUCCGACACUACCCAGAGUCAGUUUUGGAUCCCAGAUAGAGGGCUCAGUCCCCAGGACUGGCCUCUCCUUCCCACCAGUCACAAGUCCAGGCCUCUGGAACUUCUGACCAACUGGCUUCAAGUUGGGGUUCCCACGAUCCCCUCUUUGAGUUCAGUGGAUUUGCUAGAGUAGCUCAGAGAACUCAGGGAAAUACUUAUGUUUAUGGGUUUAGUGUGAUGGAUAUGUUAAAGGGUGCAAAUAAACAGCCAUAUGAAGAGAUACACAGGGCAUGGUCUGGAAGGGUCCCGAGCACAGGAGCUUCUUUCCCCGUAGAGUUGGGGUAUGCCACCCUCCCAGCAAAUGUAUGAGUUCCUGUUGAUCUUCCUGUCUGCUUCCACAUGUUCAGCUAUCCAGAUGCUCUCAGAACCUCUUCAGUUUUUAUGAAGCCUUCAUUAUGUAGGCUUGAUUGAUUAAGCCAGUGGCCGUUGGUGGUCAGCUUGACCUUUAGCACCCCUCCCUGGAGGUUGGGGGUAGGGCUGACCGUCCAACCCUCUAAUUGUACCUUUAUUUUUCAGGUGACCAGCCCCGCCCUAAAGCUGUUAGUCAAUAUUAGCAUACAAAAAUAGAGCUAUUUGGAGAUAACAAGGAGUUUAGGAGCCCUACCUCAGGAAAUAGGGAUGAAGACCAGAUACAUAUUGCACAAUAUCACACUCACUAUUUAUUCUCCUAUUCUUGGACAUUGAGGUUGUUUACAGUUUUAUAAUAUUAUGGUGUUACAGUAAGCAUUUGUGUAAAUGUCUUUUUUUGGGUCGGGGUGGGGGCAAGGUAGAGGGUCUUCCUGUGUUUUCCAGGUUGAUGUCAAACUCCUGGCCAAGGGAUCUUCCUAUUUUGAUAGGUCUUUUUAUCCACGCAUGUAUCCUGGGGUUUCUAUUUGUCCUUUCUCCUGUCUGGCAUUCCAUGACUCUUGCCUGAAUUCAGUAGCUCAAUUCUCACAUCUGAAGAAUUUUUCUUUAACUGUAACAUUUGAUUGAUGGGUCAUUUUUCUUAGCUUUAUAAAGGCAUUGCUUCAGUGCCUUUAAACUUACAGUGUUGCUGUUGAGAAAUCCAAUGCCAUAAUGAUUCCUGAUUUUUUUUAGCUGUUCUGCUUUUUUCUCUCUGGAAGCUUUCAGAAUUUCUACUACAGAAUGUCUGAGUACCAAGGAUAAUGUGCCUUGAGAUGGAUCAUUUUUCUUUAAAAAAAAUUACUAUGAAAUAUUUCAGACGCAGAUAUAAAGAAUAAUAACAAUCACUCUGGCCCAAGAAAUAAAACAUCAUCAGUGCAGUUGAACCCUACCCCCCACCACCCUUUUUUAUGUGGAAAUCCAUCCUUUAUGGAGUUUUUUCUUGUAUUACUUGUUAAUUUUCUUUCUCAGUUAUCGUUUUUUUCUGAAACUUUUAUUAAUUGUAUAUUAGGCCUCCCGAUUCAACCUCAAUUUUCUUAUCUUUCCUAUUAUAUUUUUCAUUGUCUUUUUUCCUGCUUUCUGGGGGUAGAUUUAACUAGCUUCUUAAUGUUGAUUAAUGUCAGCUGUAAUGUUUUCAGUUUGAGAGCUUGUUCUUGUUCUCUGUCCCUUUUUUAAUAACUUCCUAUUGUUUCAUGGAUACAAUACCUUUUUUCAUCUCUCUGAUACUAAUUAUACUUGUUUUUAAGUUUUCUUUUAUACUCUUAAGUUGUUCAAGUUCUUUUUUAUUUUUAUUUUAGUCUUCUGGUUAUGUUUUCAUCAAACAUGGUGAUCUGUUCAUAUUGAAACAUGAGUCGUUAUAAAACAUUAGAAACUCAGUGAACACGUGGGUGGGAUUUGUCAUUUGAAGACUGGAUAGGGAAUGUGGUCAUAUUGUGAGAAAAGCUCUAAAUAUUAGUGUUUAAAGAUAUUGUUUCUUGGGCCUUUAGUUUCUACAGCUAAAAAUCUACCACAUUUUUGUCAGGGGAUGGAGUAGGUUACACACCUGUCUGCUAGAAUUCUUGGAAGGAGGUAGGCGAUUGCAUUGUUAAAUAACUGGGAUUUUGCUUAAUUCCCUGCUUCCAGUGUAAUGGUUCUCUCCCUUGCUUGUGCCUUGUAUCCUUGUGUCUGUAGUCAUUUAGUUCACUUUUACCACAAAUAAGGUGAGGAAAAAGGAGCAUGGGAUAGGAAGGUAGAAUGUAAGUGGAAGGGUCUCACUGACUCAAGCAGAUUUUAAACCCACCUUUUUUGUUUUUAGUUGCAUGCUUUGUUCUUGCCUUCUAUAAAAGUUAGCCAGAGUUCUCAGUUUGCAAAUUUCCCUGUACAUUUUUCACCUUCCAAAAACAUUUUGAUAGCUUGUAUCUGUAGUUUUUACUUCUGUUCUCUUUGACUAUCUGGGAUUUUAGCCUUGAUAUUUUAUUCUCACUUGAGUGGGAUUUUGACAAGGAAUAGAAAAAAAUCAUACAUCCAGUCUACCAUGUUUAAACAGCAGUCCUCUUCACCUUUUCAUCUUUAUCAGAUUCUUCCUAUUAGUGUUGAAACAUGAUCACACAAAAGAGGACUUAAAUGGAAACAUAUAUUACUGUGUUCCUGGGGAAGAAGAAUCAAUAUCAGAAUGACAAUUUCUCCUAAGUUAUAAAUUGAACACCAUCCCAAUAAAAUAGAAAUAGUUGUUUUUUGAGACAACCAAGCAGAUAUUGAAGUUUAUAUGCAAAAAUAAGUAGGCAAGAACAGCCAGAAAAGAAAAAGUAACGAUGGAGGAGUGCCUUACCUGGUACCAAUAUAUUCUAAAGAUUUAAUUAUUAAAUCAGUGUAAUUAGUUUAUGAGCUCUGUUCAGCAAGAUAGAAAAUUUAGAAAUAGACUACAGGCACUCACCACCACGCCCGGCUAAUUUUUUGUAUUUUUUUAGUAGAGAUAGGGUUUCACCAUGUUGCCCAGGCUGGUCUUGAACUCCUGGACUCAAGUGAUCCGCCUGCCUUGGCCUCCCAAAGUGCUGGGAUUACAGGUGUGUGCCACAGUACCUGGCCCCCAAACAAUGGCUUAAAACAACGCAAAUUUAGUUUCUUACAGUUCUGAAGGCUCUGAGGGAAAAAAAUCAAGUUUUUGCCUUUUUUAGCUUCUUGUGUCUUACAUUUCCUAGCUUGUGGCCCCUUCCUCCAUCUUCAAAGUAUAUUACCCCAGGCUAUGCUUCUAUCAUCACAUCGCCUUCUCAAAUAUCUCUUUGCCUCAGUCUUUAAAAGACACGUGUUAUUACAUUUAAGCCCACCUGGAUAAUCCAGGAGACUCUCCCCAUCUCAGGAUCCUUAAUUUAUUCACAUCUGCAGAGUCCAUUUUGCCAUAAGGUAACAUUCACAGAUUCUGGGGAUUAGGUUCUAGGGGUUAGGUUCUUUGGAAGCCGUUUUUCAACCUAUCACAUACUUCUGGCUCAUCAUGUCCAAAACAGUGAAACCUGAUCCUCCUCCAGAAGAGAGAGUAGUUGCUCUUUCAGGUUCCAAAGUACAGAACCUGGUAGUCAUCUUUCAUACUUCUUUCUCUUAUCUAUCAUAUCCAAUCUUUGUCCACAUCUUGACAAUUUUAUCUCCUGUAUAAUUUUCAGAUCUCUUUGUUUUUCUUUUAAAAAGAAGUCCCUAUUUAAAAUCAAGUUAUUAGCUUAGCCUAACAUUUCUUAUUUGGCAUAUUAUAGAAUACUCCUAGCUGAUCUCUUUACUUUUUGUGCCCCUCUGAGAAAACUAAACAAACAAAAAACCAAAGGCAAAUUGGGUAACUUUCCUUCUUUUCAGAUCCUUUAGUGGCUUUCCAGAAUCCUUGAUGUGAUCUUCUAGGCUCUCCAUAAUCCAGCUACAGCUGAUUUUUCCAGUCUCAUCUUUAUUUUUCUCUUUUGCUUUCUGUGUUUAUUAUCAUUAGCUUUCUUUUAGAUCUUGGAAAGGGCAAUGCUUAAGAGAUUUUGUUUCCCUCUGAACUUGUUCUUCAGAUUUGAGCUCAAUGUUACUUCAAGGAAUACUUUAUUCCCCGGAUCAGGAUCCCAUGUUCUUUUUCAUAGUGUCAUACAUCUUACAUUCUGAAGAUCAAAGUUUAUAAUUAAAUGUUUAUUUAGAUUAGUGUCUGCCUCUCCUUACUAGACUGUAAGCUUCAAGUGGCCAGGAAUAGGUCUGGUUUGCUAUACCUGUGUUGAGUACAGUGGCAUAAAAUAUAUGUUUAUGUGCUAUGUAGUGACGUUUCAGUCAAUGACAGACUGCAUAUGUAACGCUGACUCCAUAAGAUUAUAAUGGAGCUGAAAAAUUCCUAUCACUUACUAUAUUUACUAUACCUUUUAUCAUUAUUUUAGAACAUACUUCUACUUAUUAAAAAAAAGUUAACUGUAAAACACCCUCAGACAGAUCUUUCAGGAGAUAUUACAGAAGAAGGCUUUGUUAUCAUAGCAGAUGAUAGCUCCGUGAGUGUUAUUGCCCCUGAAGACUUUUCAGCAGGACAAGAUGUGGAGAUGAAAGACAGUGAUAUUAAUCAUUCCAACCCUGUUGUAGGCAUAGGCCAAUGUGUGCAUUUGUAUCUUUGUUUUUAACAAAAAAGGUUUAAAAAAAGUAAAAAAAAAAGUUUUUAAGUAGAAAAUACCUUACAGAAUAAGGACGUAAAGAAAGUAUUUUUGUAUAGCUGUACAAUGUGUUUUAAACUAUGUGUUAUUACAAGAGUCAAAGAAUUAAAAAACUCAUAAAGUUUAUAAAAAUUACAGUAAGCUAAAGUUAAUUUAUUAUUGAAGAAAGAAAAAUUUUAAAAAUCAGUGUAACCUAAGUGUACACUGUUUAUAAAGUCUACAGUAGUGUACAGCAGUGUCCUAGGCCUUCACAUUCACUCACCACUCACUCACUGACCCAUAACAACUCCCUAUUCUGCAAGCAUGGGAAGUUAAAUGUGUUUAGAUACAUAAAAACUUACCAUUGUGUUUCAGGUAUCUACGGCAGGGGUCCUCAACUGUACUGGUCCCCCAGUACUGGUCUGUGGCCUGUUAAAAACCUGGCUGCAGCAAGCUAUAAUAGCAUUGCUGCUUGAGCUCCGCCUCCUGUCAGAUAACCUGCAGCAUUCGAUUCUCAUAGGAGUGUGAACUCUGUUGUGAAUUGUGCAUGCGAGGGAUCUAGGUUGCACACUUCUUAUGAGAAUAUGACUAAUGCCUGAUGAUCUGAGGUGGGUCAGUUUCAUCCAGAACCAUGCCUGCCAACCCCCUGCCCUUUUCCGUGGAAAAAUUGUCUUCCACAAAACCAGUCCCUCAUGCCAAAAAGAUUGGGGACCACUGGACUACAGUAUUCAGUACAAUAACAUGCUGUAAGUUUUGUAGCCUAGGAGCAAUAGGCUAUGUCAUAUAGCCUAGGUGUGUAGUAGGCUAUACCACUUAGAUUUGUGUAAGUACAAGCUGUGAUGUUCUCAACCACAAAUUGCCUAAUGACAUUUCUCAGAAUGUAUUUCUGUCAUUAGGUGACACAUGACUGUACAAUAAACUUGUGGUAAAUGAAUGACACCUGCUUUCCUGUAACUCAUGUUACAGGCCUCCAAGUAUUUGAAGACUGUUGUGUCCCUCCUUUAAUCUUUUCAAGUUAAAUACUUUUGAAAUACUUUUGAUUUCUUGCAUUCUUCCUCCAUUUUGUAUGGUUUGCAAGUCCCUAAUCACUUUAAAUGUUCUAUUUUGGGUGUGCCCUAGUUAUAGAUAUUUUUUAGGCCAGAUCGGGAGAUCACACCCCAGAUGAUAUCUCUGUGCAAUGCAGAAUAUUGCCUCCCUCAUUACAAAGUAUACAAGGUAUAGGCUAAAAAACCAUAACAAUGAGGACCAAUGUGCAGUGGCUAGAACAAAAGUUUGUCUCUUGUUUAGCAGUCCCGAGGUAAGCAACUCUGUUCCUUGUUGUCAUCCAGGAUGCUAGUUUCCUUCUGUCUUUAAUUUUUGUCGUUCCUACUGGUGUUGUCAUGUGCAUGAUUGAGACUAGCUCUUUACCACUCUGUGUUGCAGCCCUCAAAAGAGAAAAAGGAAGUGGAGGGCAAGCCACUUCCUUAUAAAGGUAUGCCCUGAAGAUUGCAUAUGUAACUUAUGUGACUGUCUCAUUGGCCCAAACUUAGGCACAGGCCGCAUUUAGCUGUCAGGGAGCCUAGCUUAUUGGCCAUAUGCCCAGGAAAUUUUCUUACUAAAAAGAAGGAAUACUUUGCUUGUUUGGCAUUAGUUUCCUACAGUUGGUGAAUGUUUUUUUGUUUUAUCUAUUUUUUUCUCUCUUUUUUUUUUUCUUGUCAGCCUUUUCAGGUUGAAAGUUGGUGCAUGUUGAAUUUGUGGUCAUAACUGCUGUUCAUUGUUAUGCUGUUAAUUAUUUAAAUGUAUCACAAACAUUUGCAUUUAUUAAAUUUUUAAAUGCAAGUGAUAGACUGGUAAUCAGCAGUUCUUCUUCUCCCCCUCCACCCCUUUUUUUUCUUUUUGCCAGAGUUUGUGGUUGAUUACUUCAUUUCUAGCCUUAACAUACAGAAAUUCAACAAAUAUUUAUGACUACAUACCAGGCACUUUGUAUUACAGAUAUAUAAUAUUGAAUAAUACAGAUUGUUCUCUUUCACAAAGUUUGUAUUCAAACAUAUUGCUUGAUUUCUUUUGUGAGUGGUUUAAAUUGGGGGUUGGCAAACUUUUUCUAUUAAGGACCAGAUAGUAUUUUCUGCCCUGUGGCCUAAAAUUUAUGUAAAUAAUUCAAACAACCCAAUAACAACAACAACGAAAUAAUCUGAUUUAAAAGUGGGCAAAAGACCUAAAUAGACAUUCUGAAAUUUGAAGACAUACAACAGGUAUAUGAAAAAAUGUUCAACAUAAUUCAUCAUCAGGGAAAUGGAAGUCAGAACUACAAUUAGAUAUCACCUCACCCCAGUUCUGGCUGUUAACAAAAAGACAAAAAAUAAAUGCUGGUGAGGAUAUGGAAAAAGGAGAACUUUUAUACAGUUAAUGUCAAUCUAAAUUAGUACAGACAUUAUGGUCAACAGUGUGGAUGUUCCUUAAAAAAUUAAAAAUAGAACGACCACAUGACCAAGCAAUUCCACUUCUUGGUAUAUGUCCAACUCAAGGAAAUUUAAUCAGUAUGUUGAAGAUCUGCAUUUCCAUGUUUAUUGCAGCACUAUUCAUAACAGCCAGUUUGUUUUUCUUAAAAAAUAGUUGUCCUUGACCAUUUUUGAAACGUUAUUCUUACAUCAUUUUAAUUGCAUUACUUCUUAACUCAUCCUUUCACAAUUUCUUUAGCUAACUCUUCCUCCUGUCUGUCAAAUAUCUGUUUUCCUUUAAGUGCAGUUCUUGGUUCUGUCUCUUUCUAUUCUUUCUCUCAAGUCUUAGUCACUUAAAAAAUUAUAUGUUAUAGACAAUUUCCAAAUCUAUGCAUCUAUUCCUUACCUUUUUUGAUCUAGUUAUAACUCCAAAUCUAACUUACCUAAAAUCUGUAAAUGUUAUGUACUUUCGUUCUUUGAGCUUGAAACCUUAUUUUGAGUCAUUUUAUACCAUCAAGGAAAUAUAGGAGUUGUAAAGGUGGACAAUAACAUGUGAAAACUUGUGGAGGCAGCAGAAAUUAUUUAGAAUUUGCGAAAUGUAUAUUUAGAAUGUGGCAAAUGUGGAGAAUGUGGCAAAUCUUGGUCUGUUAUUCCCUUGGAAUAAUAGAUCAGGAGGGGCUUUGUCUUCCUUAAAAAGGAUUUUCUAGUUUGAUGCUACAGGUAAUAUGGAGCUACUAAAGGAUUUAAAAUGGGAAGGUUGAAUGAUAAGAUGUUUUUUCCUAGAUUAUUUGUAGCAGUAUGUAGGAUGGCUCUUGGGGAUAGGAAUCCUGAAGCAAGGAUACUGGUUAAGAGGUUUUACAAUUAGGUGAGAAAUGAUAAUUUCCUGAAUUAAGGCAGUGGUACUGCAGAUUUAGUUAGAAGGAUAGAUUUUGAUUUAAGUGAUGAGGAAGAGGGAUUUAUCAAUUCCUGAUUUAGGACCUGAGAAAAUGAAUAUUAUUAACCGGCGAAGUACAUACAGAAGGAGAAAAAGAAGGUUUGGGAGGGGAAGGGAACCUUACAAAAAAACGAGCUCUGUUUUGUAGGUAUUAAAUUUGAGGGUGUCUGUGGGCUGCCCAGGAGGCAUUUGUAUGUUAAGAUCUGAAUCUGAGGCAGAGUUUUAAGUUAGAGAUGUAGAUAUGGAAUGUAGUAGGGUACAGGUGGUAGUUAAAUCUGUAGUAUAAUUGAAACCACCCACAGAUAAUAUGUGGAAUGAAAACUGGGCCAACUCUGCAACAACCACGUUUUGGAGAGGAGGAAGCCUGGAAAGGGAAAUCAAGAAAGCAGGUGAUUGCAAAGCAUUCCUUGAAUUUGGUUGUGAAGAGGUCAUCAGUGAUUUGUUUCAGGGGAGUGGUAUGGGCAGAAGCCUGAUUGCAAUGAUAUGAGAUGUGAAUAAAAGGUGAGGUGAGGCAAUAGAGACAGGUACUACAGACUAGUAUUACAGAAGUAGGAUUCUUAUGUGAAAAAGGUAUAUAUAUCUUGGUGCUUUUGAUGGCAAGUUGCAGGAUAGUCAAUUUUAAAAUGGGCUUAAAUGAUGAAAGAGAUUUAUUGGCCUAUGGAAUGGAAAAGUCCAGAGGUGGGAUGGAUAGUUUGAAUGUUUCAGGCCUGGGGUUUGCAGGCAGGGCUGGUGGAAGGACUGGGAUAGAGGAUGAGAGUGUGUUUAUGAGAGAGGGAUAAACCUUGAGGUUUAGACUAGAUAUGGAAGCAGCUGAAAGAAGGAGGGGACUGAUACUGAGAAAAAAACGUAGGUCACAGAAAGCUAGAGGUCUAAUUUCAUGUAAGUAAAGGAAUGAAAACAGGAAGGUUGUGGUUUACUAAUAAGGGCUUUCUCUAGCUAGGCUAAGUUAGCUACAGUUAUCCAAAUAGGCUUUAUACAUUGCAGCUUUCAAAAUCCAGUCCUAGUAUUUUGUAGCAUAGUUGUUUACUUGAUGGCUCUUCUGCCAGGAAAUAAAAAUUGAACAUUGUUAAUUCUUUGUCACUCAUGGAUACAACAUUGGUACUCACACAAAGGUGUGAACCUGAAGAUCCUCGUAAGAUGAGAAGCUUUUCUUUGUGUAUAUAUGAAAAUAAACAUGUUGGUCUUGGCGAAAUUAUGAGGUCGCUAUAUUUUGUGGUCAUACCCUUUCUUUGUCUUCUGUUGCUCCCGCCUUCCUCUUUUUUAGGUUUACUUUUUAUUCUCUUUGCAAAUAGGAAAAGAUGCUUCAUAUUUAUUCAUGUCACAUGUUGAUUAUUCUAGGUGUUUACCUUUCUAAGUUGUCUUCAAGUUCAGUGCUGUUGAGUUUAGUGGUGUUUGAAUUAGGUAAACUUGGAGUGGUGUGAUAUAAGAAUAUUAAUUCAGUCUCACUUUGUGUGUAAAAUUUAAAGUAGUAUGAAUUCCUUCAAAUUAAUAAUGCAUUGAGUUGUAUAAUCUCAGGCCAAGUAAAUUGAAAACUGCCACAUGGCAGUGUACUUCUUUAGGAUUGGUCUUGAGUUUUGGCUGCUUUAAAUUAGGAUAGGUCUUAAGAGUCACUUCUGGCUGGGAAAAAGAUUUUAAAAAGAUCAUGAUAGGUCUUUAGGACAUUUGUCCCAUAAAAUGCCUGUAUAGAGAGAAAGCCUUUCUUAGUAAAGGAAUUUCUGAGACUGGGAAUAGUUGGGAGAGGUGUUUGGGGGAGACUGAUAUUUCUUUUUUUUUUUUUGAGACGGAGUCUUGCCCUGUCGCCCAGGCUGGAGUGCAGUGGCACGAUCUUGGCUCACUGCAAACUCCGCCUCCCAUGUUCAAGCAGUUCUCUGCCUCAGCCUCCCGAGUAUCUGGGACUACAGGCAUGCACCACCGUGCCUGGCUAAUUUUUGUAUUUUUAGUAGAGACGGGAUUUCACCAUCUCGGCCAGGCUGGUCUUGAGCUCCUGACAUCAUGAUACACCUGCUUUGGCCUCCCAAAGUGCUGGGAUUACAGGCAUGCACCACCGUGCCUGGCCGAGACUGAUAAUUUCUUAUUACCCCUAAAAGCAUAUGAUUCCUAGAAAUGUUGCUGAAGGUUAAAUCUACUUUAGUUGUUUUAGAGUGCUUAGAAAGGUUAGAAUAAUGAUUUAAAAAGACUUACCUUUCUUCCCCUUCCUUAUCUCUAUAUCCCAUGAUGAGCCUUUGUUCCAUGCUGCCACCCCUGGCUUUUUAUGGCAUGAUGAUCAUACCAAACUUAUGGAAAGUAAUUCAUAUGAAUAUAUAUAAAGUAAUUCUGGCCUGGGUGGCUGCUGCUUAAGAAUCAUCUAAAGUGAUCUUGGGGGGAGGAUUUGUAAGGAAUUAAAAAAUCCCUACCCCUGCUAUUUGAGAACAAGAUCUACAGCCUUUUUUUCUGUGUAUAUAUGUGUGGGUGAUGUUAAAUUGUCUAUGGAAAAAAAUUGAUUCUAAAAAUGCUGCUAAAGAACAAAUGGUGAAGAAUUGUGGUAAGAUAUCCUAGAUGGUCAUUUAUGUAGACUGUUUCCUAUUAAGGCAAAAUAGGUGGUAUUUAAAACAUGACAGUAGAUUCUUUAAAUUUUUUUUAAUGUUCAUUAAAGAGCCAUUUUAUAUAAAGGUACAGCUAUAUGUUAGGCUUUUAAAUUUAAUCUGCAUUUUAACAGAGGUAGAAAAUGCUAGGUAACUGAUCUGAAGUGGAAAUUCUGGUUAAAUACAGCAUUUCUAGUCUAGUCCAUUGCUAUGUACAGGAUCCAUCUCUCUAUCCUUGAGAAACUCUAAAUUGGAGAUUACAUAAGAUAAGAACAUACAUGAAAUGACUAGAGGAAUAGUAUCAGAUUGUAUGGAAUUAAUGAUAGAUUCCAUUCAGAUGCUAGAUAGGAUGCUCUGGGCUGCAUAUUUAUGUAGGAUAUGUCCUAAAUUCACUGGAGAGUUGAUAUAGAGAAAAUAUAUGUUGCUCAUAGGUAACAUUAGACUUCAGAGAAGGGAGAGAUCAUGGAGUGUGACCAGAAAGACUUCUGGAAAAAAAGAGCUUUUGAACUGCUCUUUGAAAGAUGGAUACGAUUUGGGUUGACAGAAAAGAGGACAUUCCAGAUUGGGCAGAUUCAAGAGAAAAAUCACUGGAGGUAGAAAUAAGUUUGUCAUAAGUUGAGUAGAGAAAAAGAUUGGGGCCAGGCUUGGUGGCUCACACCUGUACUCCUAAAACUUUGGGAGGCCAAGGCGGGUGGAUCACUUGAGGUCAGGAGUUCAAGACCAGCCUGGCCAACGUGUUGAAACCCCAUCUCUACUAAAAAAAUACAAAAAUUAGCCAGGCAUGGUGGCGCACACCUGUAAUUCCAGCUACUUGGGAGGCUGAGGGAGGAGAAUUGCUUGAAUUGGGAGGUGGAGGUUGCAGUGAGCUGAGAUCAUGCCAUUGCACUCCAGCCUGUGGGACAAAGAGUGAAACUCCAUCUCAAAAAAAAGGAAAAAAAAAAAAAAAAGAUUGGCCUGUCUUGGUAACAGUGAGCCUCGUAUCCUGGUAUCUGGGCUAAAGUGAAGACUUUGAAGCUAGGGAGUACAAAAUGAACAUGGAAGAUUAAUAUGACUAUGGUCUUUUUUUCUCCCUGCCCUGAUGAUUUUACUUUUAUAUGUUUUUUUCUUAAAUAAAGAUCACACUCUAAAAUAUUACAAAGUUAAAAAAAUCAUUUUUAGAGAAGUUUAAGUAUUAAAUAGAUAUUAAUGUCUUCAAUGUUUCUUUGAGAUCUUCAGGUUAAAUCACACAUUGAAAUUUGCUUGUGGCAUAUGUAUUAGUGUAUUUGUCAGUGUGCUUGGGUGCCUCUCUGACUUUAUUCAAGGUAUUGACCAUUCAGUUCUUAGUUUGUAGAAGAAAUGGCAACGUUGGAAACAAUAACCUAUUUUAAUUCUUUAAUUAUAUUAUAGUUGUACCUCAGUCCAUUUUUCCCUCUUUUG